ACAGUGGUCCUCCGCCGGCUACGCCGCUGCCUCAGUGGCUUUCAGGCGCUUUCCUCUUGGAAUUGGCGACUGCUGCGGGGCUGAGCGCUGGUCUCACGCAUCUCGGGAGCCAGGUUGGUGGCGCGAUGAGUUGCAGCAAGGCCUACGGGGAGCGGUACGUCGCCUCGGUGCAGGGCUCCGCCCCGUCGCCUCGAAAGAAGUCAACGAGAGGAUUCUAUUUUGCAAAGCUGUAUUAUGAAGCUAAAGAAUAUGAUCUUGCUAAAAAAUACAUAUGUACUUACAUUAAUGUGCGAGAGAUGGAUCCCAGAGCUCACAGAUUUCUGGGUCUUCUUUAUGAAUUGGAAGAAAACACAGAGAAAGCCGUUGAAUGUUACAGGCGUUCAGUGGAAUUAAACCCAACACAAAAAGAUCUUGUGUUGAAGAUUGCAGAAUUGCUUUGUAAAAAUGAUGUUACUGAUGGAAGAGCAGAAUACUGGGUGGAAAGAGCAGCAAAACUUUUCCCAGGAAGUCCUGCAAUUUAUAAACUAAAGGAACAGCUUCUAGAUUGUGAAGGUGAAGAUGGAUGGAAUAAACUUUUUGACUUGAUUCAGUCAGAACUUUAUGUAAGACCUGAUGACGUCCAUGUGAACAUCCGGCUAGUGGAGUUGUAUCGCUCAACUAAAAGAUUGAAGGAUGCUGUGGCCCGCUGCCAUGAGGCAGAGAGGAACAUAGCUUUGCGUUCAAGUUUAGAGUGGAAUUCGUGUGUUGUACAGACCCUUAAGGAAUAUCUGGAGUCUUUACAGUGUUUGGAGUCUGAUAAAAGUGACUGGCGAGCAACCAAUACAGACUUACUGCUGGCCUAUGCUAAUCUUAUGCUUCUUACGCUUUCCACUAGAGAUGUGCAGGAAAGUAGAGAAUUACUGGAAAGUUUUGAUAGUGCUCUUCAGUCUGCGAAAUCUUCUUUGGGUGGAAAUGAUGAACUGUCAGCUACUUUCUUAGAAAUGAAAGGACAUUUCUACAUGCAUGCUGGUUCUCUGCUCUUGAAGAUGGGUCAGCAUGGUAAUAAUGUUCAAUGGCGAGCUCUUUCUGAGCUGGCUGCAUUGUGCUAUCUCAUAGCAUUUCAGGUUCCAAGACCAAAGAUUAAAUUAAUAAAAGGUGAAGCUGGACAAAAUCUGCUGGAAAUGAUGGCCUGUGACCGACUGAGCCAAUCAGGGCACAUGUUGCUAAACUUAAGUCGUGGCAAGCAAGAUUUUUUAAAAGUGGUUGUUGAAACUUUUGCCAACAAAAGCGGGCAGUCUGCAUUAUAUGAUGCUCUGUUUUCUAGUCAGUCACCUAAGGAUACAUCUUUUCUUGGUAGCGAUGAUAUUGGAAACAUUGAUGUACAAGAACCAGAGCUUGAAGAUUUGGCUAGAUACGAUGUUGGUGCUAUUCGAGCACAUAAUGGUAGUCUUCAGCACCUUACUUGGCUUGGCUUACAGUGGAAUUCAUUGCCUGCUUUACCUGGAAUCCGAAAAUGGCUAAAACAGCUUUUCCAUCAUUUGCCCCAGGAAACCUCAAGGCUUGAAACAAAUGCACCUGAAUCAAUAUGUAUUUUAGAUCUUGAAGUAUUUCUCCUUGGAGUAGUAUAUACCAGCCACUUACAAUUAAAGGAGAAAUGUAAUUCUCACCACAGCUCCUAUCAGCCGUUAUGCCUGCCCCUUCCUGUGUGUAAACAGCUUUGUACAGAAAGACAAAAAUCUUGGUGGGAUGCGGUUUGUACUCUGAUUCACAGAAAAGCAGUACCUGGAAACUCAGCAAAAUUGAGACUUCUAGUUCAGCAUGAAAUAAACACUCUAAGAGCCCAGGAAAAACAUGGCCUUCAACCUGCUCUGCUUGUACAUUGGGCAAAAUGCCUUCAGAAAAUGGGCAGCGGUCUUAAUUCUUUUUAUGAUCAACGAGAAUACAUAGGGAGAAGUGUUCAUUAUUGGAAGAAAGUUUUGCCAUUGUUGAAGAUAAUAAAAAAGAAGAACAGUAUUCCUGAACCUAUUGAUCCUCUGUUUAAACAUUUUCAUAGUGUAGACAUUCAGGCAUCAGAAAUUGUUGAAUAUGAAGAAGACGCACACGUAACUUUUGCUAUAUUGGAUGCAGUAAAUGGAAAUAUAGAAGAUGCUAUGACUGCUUUUGAAUCUAUAAAAAGUGUUGUUUCUUAUUGGAAUCUUGCACUGAUUUUUCACAGGAAGGCAGAAGACAUUGCAAAUGAUGCCCUUUCUCCUGAAGAACAAGAAGAAUGCAAAAAUUAUCUGAGAAAGACCAGGGGCUACCUAAUAAAGAUUUUAGAUGACAGUGAUUCAAAUCUUUCAGUGGUCAAGAAAUUGCCUGUGCCCCUGGAGUCUGUAAAAGAGAUGCUUAAGUCAGUCAUGCAGGAACUCGAAAACUAUAGUGAAGGAGGUCCUCUCUAUAAAAAUGGUUCUUUGCGAAAUGCGGAUUCAGAAAUAAAACAUUCUACACCAUCUCCUACCAAAUAUUCACUAUCACCAAGUAAAAGUUACAAGUAUUCUCCCAAAACACCACCUCGAUGGGCAGAAGAUCAGAAUUCUUUACUGAAAAUGAUUCGCCAAGAAGUAAAGGCCAUUAAGGAAGAAAUGCAGGAGUUGAAACUAAAUAGCAGUAAGUCAGCAUCCCAUCAUCGUUGGCCCACAGAGAAUUAUGGACCAGACUCGGUGCCUGAUGGAUAUCAGGGGUCACAGACAUUUCAUGGGGCUCCACUAACAGUUGCAACUACUGGCCCUUCAGUAUAUUAUAGUCAGUCACCAGCAUAUAAUUCCCAGUAUCUUCUCAGACCAGCAGCUAAUGUUACUCCCACAAAGGGUUCUUCUAAUACAGAAUUUAAGUCAACCAAAGAAGGAUUUUCCAUCCCUGUGUCUGCUGAUGGAUUUAAAUUUGGCAUUUCGGAACCAGGAAAUCAAGAAAAGAAAAGUGAAAAGCCUCUUGAAAAUGAUACUGGCUUACAGGCUCAGGAUAUUAGUGGCCGGAAGAAGGGCCGUGGUGUGAUUUUUGGCCAAACAAGUAGCACUUUUACAUUUGCAGAUGUUGCAAAAUCAACUUCAGGAGAAGGAUUUCAGUUUGGCAAAAAAGACCUCAAUUUCAAGGGAUUUUCAGGUGCUGGAGAAAAAUUAUUCUCAUCACAAUACGGUAAAAUGGCCAAUAAAGCAAACACUUCCGGUGACUUUGAGAAAGAUGAUGAUGCCUAUAAGACUGAGGACAGCGAUGACAUCCAUUUUGAACCAGUAGUUCAAAUGCCUGAAAAAGUAGAACUUGUAACAGGAGAAGAAGGUGAAAAAGUUCUGUAUUCACAGGGGGUAAAACUAUUUAGAUUUGAUGCUGAGGUAAGUCAGUGGAAAGAAAGGGGCUUGGGGAACUUAAAAAUUCUCAAAAACGAGGUCAAUGGCAAAGUAAGAAUGCUGAUGCAAAGAGAACAAGUACUAAAAGUGUGUGCUAAUCAUUGGAUAACGACUACAAUGAACCUGAAGCCCCUCUCUGGAUCAGAUAGAGCAUGGAUGUGGUCAGCCAGUGAUUUCUCUGAUGGUGAUGCCAAACUAGAGCGAUUGGCAGCAAAAUUUAAAACACCAGAGCUGGCUGAAGAAUUCAAGCAGAAAUUUGAGGAAUGCCAGCGGCUUCUGUUAGACAUACCACUUCAAACUCCCCAUAAACUUGUAGAUACUGGCAGAGCUGCCAAGUUAAUACAGAGAGCUGAAGAAAUGAAGAGUGGACUGAAAGAUUUCAAAACAUUUUUGACAAAUGAUCAAACAAAAGUCGCUGAGGAAGAAAAUAAGGGUUCAGGUACAGGUGCGGCCGGUGCCUCAGACACAACAAUAAAACCCAAUGCUGAAAACACUGGGCCCACAUUAGAAUGGGAUAACUAUGAUUUAAGGGAAGAUGCUUUGGAUGAUAGUGUCAGUAGUAGCUCAGUACAUGCUUCUCCAUUGGCAAGUAGCCCUGUGAGAAAAAAUCUUUUCCACUUUGAUGAGUCAACAACAGGAUCUAACUUCAGUUUUAAAUCUGCUUUGAGUCUAUCUAAGUCUCCUGCCAAGUUGAAUCAGAGUGGGACUUCAGUUGGCACUGAUGAAGAAUCUGAUGUUACUCAAGAAGAAGAGAGAGAUGGACAGUACUUUGAACCUGUUGUUCCUUUACCUGAUCUAGUUGAAGUAUCCAGUGGUGAGGAAAAUGAACAAGUUGUUUUUAGUCACAGGGCAGAAUUCUACAGAUAUGAUAAAGAUGUUGGUCAAUGGAAAGAAAGGGGCAUUGGUGAUAUAAAGAUUUUACAGAAUUAUGAUAAUAAGCACGUUCGUAUACUGAUGAGAAGGGACCAAGUAUUAAAACUUUGUGCCAAUCACAGAAUAACUCCAGACAUGAGUUUGCAAAAUAUGAAAGGGACAGAAAGAGUAUGGGUGUGGACUGCAUGUGAUUUUGCAGAUGGAGAAAGAAAAGUAGAGCAUUUAGCUGUUCGUUUUAAACUACAGGAUGUUGCAGACUCGUUUAAGAAAAUUUUUGAUGAAGCAAAAACAGCCCAGGAAAAAGAUUCUUUGAUAACACCUCAUGUUUCUCGGUCAAGCACUCCCAGAGAGUCACCAUGUGGCAAAAUUGCUGUAGCUGUAUUAGAAGAAACCACAAGAGAGAGGACAGAUGUUAUUCAGGGUGAUGAUGUAGCAGAUGCAGCUUCAGAAGUUGAAGUGUCUAGCACAUCUGAAACAACAACAAAAGCAGUGGUUUCUCCUCCAAAGUUUGUAUUUGGUUCAGAGUCUGUUAAAAGAAUUUUUAGUAGUGAAAAAUCAAAACCAUUUGCAUUUGGCAACAGUUCUGCCACUGGGUCUUUGUUUGGAUUUAGUUUUAAUGCACCUUUGAAAAGUAACAAUAGUGAAACUAGUUCAGUAGCCCAGAGUGGAUCUGAAAGCAAAGUGGAACCUAAAAAAUGUGAACUGUCAAAGAACUCUGAUAUCGAACAGUCUUCAGAUAGCAAAGUCAAAAAUCUCUCUGCUUCCUUUCCAACGGAAGAAUCUUCAAUCAACUACACAUUUAAAACACCAGAAAAGGAGCCUCCAUUAUGGUAUGCUGAAUUUACUAAAGAAGAAUUGGUUCAGAAGCUCAGUUCCACCACAAAAAGUGCAGAUCACUUAAACGGCCUGCUUCGGGAAAUAGAGGCAACCAAUGCAGUCCUUAUGGAGCAAAUUAAGCUUCUCAAAAGUGAAAUAAGAAGAUUGGAAAGGAAUCAAGAGCAAGAGGUGUCUGCAGCUAACGUGGAACACUUGAAGAACGUCUUGCUGCAGUUCAUUUUCUUGAAGCCAGGUAGUGAAAGAGAGAGACUUCUUCCUGUUAUAAAUACGAUGUUGCAGCUCAGCCUUGAAGAAAAGGGAAAACUUGCUGCGGUUGCUCAAGGUGAGGAAUAAAAUGCUUCCCGUUCUUCUGGAUGGGCAUCCUAUCUUCGUAGUUGGUUUGGACUUCGAUAGGUUGAUGGAAGGAAUGUUUUUAUUAACCAAAUAAAAUCUAUUUACAAAAAUGGUUCAUGUGUAUUACCAUCAUUCUUUUGUCAAAAAGUGUGUAUAUGUUUGCAUUUACAUAUAUUUGUACAUCUAUAUGACAGAUGUAUUUUAAAAGUUUCAACUUGAAGUAAAAGUACAACAGCUUGAAGUGUUGAUACCAGGCCACAGCCCUCUAACUCAUGUGAUCUCCCAUGCAUGCUGCCAGAAUAAAACCACCAGGAAUGAAUUCACUCCCCACUUCUCUGGAACCUCAGGACCCGCCCAUUUCUCGGCAGUACUGUGAAUUUUGAAGUUAAACUAAAUUUUGGUACCAUACCAACUGGAAUUUAGGCUUUAAAAAUAAUGUUUCAAGGCCAGGUGUGGUGAUUCAUGCCUGAAAUCCCACUACUUGGGGAGGCUGAGGCUGGAGAAUCGUUUGAGGCUAGUGAGCUGUGAUUGUAUCACUGCACUCCAGCUCGGGGAACAGAGCGAGACCUUGUCUCUAAAAAUAAUAAUAGUAAUAAAAAUAACAUUUUAUGACUAUUUAUUGCAAGGUCAGAUUUACAGAUUGUUAUAAAUUGUUGAGAAAUUUUUGUGAUUAGAAUAUGAAGGAAAAAGCUUUGUUGGUAAAAGUGACAUGUUAAGGGGCUAUGAAGUAAAUAUGCUGCAGUUAAUUGUGCUAAGUUAAAAUACAGUUUAGUUAUUUGCUUUAAAAUAAACUCUUCUUUUUUUCUUUAAAGUAUACUAUCUCAAAACUCAUUAUGUUGUCAGAGCCCUAGAGCUGGCUAGUGUAACACUGACUAUGAAUAGGUGGGCCCACCACUUGAGUUGAGGUGAUUUCAUGGUGUCUUUCCAGGCUCUUGAUAGGGUGUCACUGCAUGCAAGCCAUGAAUCUGUUUUGAGAAUCCUCUCCAUUUUCCCAAAUAAAAACCUAUCCCAACAGUGACUAUAUCACUCAGCAUUGAAUCUAAAUAUAAAAGUGGUGCUUUCAGUGUUUUUGGCAGAUAGUGUUCCAUAAGCUUUCCAUCAGAAGGGAUUUUAGACACCUUAGAGGUCCGUGCUACAUCUUCACAGUUCCUCUGAAUAACCUUAGGUGGUAGUGUUACUUGCCUUUGACACCGCUGCAUAUGUUUUAAUGACUAGAUCCAAACUGUGUUGUUCUUAAAUCAAAAAUUGGAUAAUUUUUAAUAUUUAUGUAUUAAUCACAUAGUAUGCUCUCUGAAGUUCUCUUAAGCCUUCAGUUUAUACUCUUAAUUUUCUUUCUGAGCUGGGGAACUGACUUUGCACUUUGGUUACACAGAACAUUGGUUUCCAAUUUAGUUUAACUGAAAUUUGCUGCUGAUAUGUUGAGUUUGUUCUUUAAAAAAUAUCUCAUAUAUCUCGUCUUUCCUCCUUAGAAGAACAGACCUAACUAGCGAAUGUAUGAAUGAAAAUGCAUCUAUUUCAGAGCCGACAUGAAGAGUUUAGUUUUUUUACUUUAUAAACUGUGAAUAUGAGUAUGCCAGCUGCAUACGAUGUAACUAAUCAUAUUUAAAUAUAUUUCACUUUCUCUUUGACUUGAGACCUUUUGAAGUCUGUAUAAACUUGUUUUGAAAUAUAGUCUCCACUUACAAAUGUCAUAACAAAAUACUUUUUUGCAUGAUAAAAAAUUGAUUACAAAAGGCAUAUUCUUUCAUGGUUUCUGCAAUGAGAGGAAGUGUAAUGAUUAUUUUAAUAUUUCUAUUAAAUAUGUUUAACUGUA